GGCAGUGGGACUGGGUUUGAGCUGGGCUUAUCCUCCAACUGUGAGGGAGGCUACAGCACACUCCACCCCACUCUCAGGGCUGGGAAUUGUUGUGGCUCAGCUAUUUGGGGGAAUCUGUUUUCCAGUUUCUCAGAACCAGCGCAAGCACACACAUCCCAGGCUCACACCCCUGGUGGCUGGACUUGCUCCCGGAUAGCCUCAGUCAGGGAGAGGCAGAGCUGCCUGGAGCCUGCUGGGCUGGUGGAAGCCUUGGUGGAUUCUGGCAGGCCAAUUAUAGACGAAUGGCCUGGGGAACCCGUGCAGCCCUUGGCUGAGUGGUUCUAAGCCCCAGCACGUCUGCCUCUGGCUUCACCCAGCCUCCUUUUCUAACUGCCCUUCUCUCCUCCCCAUCAGUGAGGACCAGACACCACUGAUUGCAGGAAUGUGUUCCCUCCCCAUGGCAAGAUACUACAUAAUUAAAUAUGCAGACCAGAAGGCUCUAUACACAAGAGAUGGCCAGCUGCUGGUGGGAGAUCCUGUUGCAGACAACUGCUGUGCAGAGAAGAUCUGCAUACUUCCUAACAGAGGCUUGGCCCGCACCAAGGUCCCCAUUUUCCUGGGGAUCCAGGGAGGGAGCCGCUGCCUGGCAUGUGUGGAGACAGAAGAGGGGCCUUCCCUACAGCUGGAGGAUGUGAACAUUGAGGAACUGUACAAAGGUGGUGAAGAGGCCACACGCUUCACCUUCUUCCAGAGCAGCUCAGGCUCCGCCUUCAGGCUUGAGGCUGCUGCCUGGCCUGGCUGGUUCCUGUGUGGCCCGGCAGAGCCCCAGCAGCCAGUACAGCUCACCAAGGAGAGUGAGCCCUCAGCCCGUACCAAGUUUUACUUUGAACAGAGCUGGUAGGGAGACAGGAAACUGCGUUUUAGCCUUGUGCCCCCAAACCAAGCUCAUCCUGCUCAGGGUCUAUGGUAGGCAGAAUAAUGUCCCCCGAAAUAUGUCCACAUCCUAAUCCCAAGAUCUGUGCAUAUGUUACCAUACAUGUCCAAAGAGGUUUUGCAAAUGUGAUUAUGUUAAGGAUCUUGAAAUGAGGAGACAAUCCUGGGUUAUCCUUGUGGGCUCAGUUUAAUCACAAGAAGGAGGCAGGAAGGGAGAGUCAGAGAGAGAAUGGAAGAUACCAUGCUUCUAAUUUUGAAGAUGGAGUGAGGGGCCUUGAGCCAACAAAUGCAGGUGUUUUUAGAAGGUGGAAAAGCCAAGGGAACGGAUUCUCCUCUAGAGUCUCCGGAAGGAACACAGCUCUUGACACAUGGAUUUCAGCUCAGUGACACCCAUUUCAGACUUCUGACCUCCACAACUAUAAAAUAAUAAACUUGUGUUAUUGUAAA